AGUCCACUUCCGGUCUCCGGGGUCGACGACAUAGCGGGUCGUAUUUUUAUCCAAAAGAAGGACCUGGAGGAGGAUGAGAGCGUUACUGCUGCACACCUAAAGUCAAGGAACAGGAGCAUUGGGAAUAUGUGAUUCAUUGCGACUGCUGGUUGUAUAUUAAGAAAAUGAGUGAGGGGCUCAAAUGAUCUAGGACAGAAAUUCUUUCUUUUUAAAUCGACAGAUAUAAUUGUAUGUAUUUAUCAUGUGCAACAUGAAGUUUUAUGGGGAGAAGCCCGAGGAAGAUUGACCAGUUUUGUAAUUCUAGCAACAUGGUCCAUGGAUCAGUGACAUUCAGGGAUGUGGCCAUUGACUUCUCUCAGGAGGAGUGGGAGUGCCUGCAGCCUGAUCAGAGGACCUUGUACAGGGAUGUGAUGUUGGAGAACUACAGCCACCUGAUCUCACUGGGAAGUUCCAUUUCUAAACCAGAUGUAAUUACGUUACUAGAGCAAGAGAAAGAGCCCUGGAUGGUUGUAAGGAAAGAAACAAGCAGACGGUAUCCAGAUUUGGAGUUAAAAUAUGGACCUGAGAAAGUAUCUCCAGAAAAUGAUACCUCUGAAGUAAAUUUACCCAAACAGAUUUCUUCAUUGGCUUCCAAACCAUCUUUUACAGCUAUUCAUAUUCAAAGGAGAAUCCAUUGCAGAAUCUGCAUUGCAUUUGGUUAUCUCUCUUUAGUGUAUUGUAGCCUGGAAAUCCUAUGAAUGUAGGCGCUCAAAUUUUGUUGCAAGAUUUAAUAGAGUGAAAACAGAGCUCCCAUACAAAGGGAGGGGACCCAAAGAGGGUAGUCGUUGCCGGCUCGAAUGCCUGGGUUUAUAUCCUGAUCAUUGUCCCUCCCGCUGUGCUCUCAGGCAAUAGAUGAUUGGCUAUUUCUUUACCUCCUGUUUUUGCCUAAUUAGCAUUUUAGCGGGCUCUCUUUCUUACCUGAUGGGUCGGGUGUGAGCUGAGUUGCAAGCCCCGUGUUUAAAGGUGGAUGUGGUCAACUUCCCAUCUAGGCUUAGGGAUUCUUAAUCGGCCUAGGAAAUCCUGCUAGUCCUGUUUCUCAGUACCCCCUCUCAACAGGAAAACCCAAGUGCUGUUGGGGAGGUUGGCCAACAACUGCUCUAAUUGCUUCCUGCUGAAUUGGGGUGUAGUAGGGGUUGUGCAGUUGAGAUUUCCUCUGGAGGGGUGCCUUCGAUGUCAUUAACAUUGGAGCAUGGGCUAGCAGGCCGGUCCAGGGGUCCGCGGUAGAUUUUAGUCAUGGACUGCAUCUGGGGCUCCAUUUGAAGAAUGAGUUGUGGCUUUACAGCUUCGAUUCUGGAAAAGACAAACUUAACAAGGAGGUUAAAGAUACAGAGAUUGAAAUGUAUGGCCUGCAGUGCAGGGGAUUAUUUCUUUGGCACACUUCACAGGCCCUGACUAUCUGCUUGAUAGUUUUGAAAAGGCCUGGUCCAUCUCCUCAUUCUUAAAAAAUGAGAUUGAAUUUUGAUUAGCCCAGGAAAAUUGUCUAUGUGUUUAGAUUUCUUUCUUUAUAGUGUCAUUUAGUGUUGUUCUCUUUGUUGCAUAUUCUGUACAAGGGAAUUUGAGUCCAGAGGCUCUGUUAGGUCAGAUUAAACAUUUUGGGGAAGAAUACUUUGUAGGCUAUUUGUAUGGCAUAUUUCACUGUCAGAAAACAUUUAAGUACAGGUCCUUGCAUUAGUGAAACUAAGUUUGAUCAUUUGGGUAAGCUGGUAACCGCCAUAAGUCCAUUGUAAAGAUCUAAUUUGUAGUGCAUAAAUAAUCUAUGGAGAGACUUUGACCUCUGAAUAUUUAUAAUCAUGUGUAUUUUAGCUGUGGAUUGAAUACAAAAUGAAAAUUGAAAUAGACUAUUCAAAAAUGAAUGCCAUUAAGGUUGUCAACAUAAGUCAACUUGUGUGAUAAGGCUGACAGUAUAUUCAGUACAAAAUUAGCACCCUCUAGUUUAUUCAGGGAGCCAAGAUUAUUUUGUCUGGAACCUUGUUUUUGUUCAGCAUUUAUCAUCAGCACCUAUACAUCAUGGCUGGUAUGUGAGCUGUUGAUAAACUUUGAAAAAAAUUAAGCCUUUAAAUCAAGCUAUAAAACAUGAUACCAUUGUGGCAUCAUGAAUUAGAGAGAUUAACUUUUUUAAAGAUCAAUAAUAAUCCUUUGUGAUUUUAUUCCAGUGCAUUUAAAAAUCUAUAAAAUGAUAAUUUAUAUUGAUAGCUUUCUUCUUUUUGUGAAUAUAUCCUUAUCAGAUUAUUAUGCUUUUGAUAGACUACUUAAUUCUAUUUCUUAACAUUUAAUUGUAUCUAUAAUCAUAGGUAAAGUUAUAAUUUUCUAAACAUUUUUCAGGUUUUGUUAAUGCAGUGAUCUUAUAAAUCUUACAAAACGAGGCUAUUUAAAACCUGGCUUUCUAGUCUCAUGUUCCUAUUUUUUAUUUCCACUUUCAUCUUUUUCAUAUUGAUUCUCUUUGACUUUCUUUUUUGAACUCAACAGAUUCCCUGGGUAUUAACCCAGCACAACUCCUUUAUGGGUCAUUGCACAUUCUGGUAUCUCAUUAAGAAUUGUCAUAAAAAAGAGAUCCCAGGAGGCCUUCCAGUGAAACUCUAUCAUCAUGCAAUCUUGGGAUUUCUAAGUUGGAAGUCACAGUCCCUUUGCAAACAUAAUAAAACACUUUAAAAUAUUUGCUAAAGUUACAAACCAAUUAUGUAAAAAUUUAAAAAUCACCUACUACUUUUAAAAGCAGAGAAGGCAUCCAUAGACUAUUUCCUUGCUUACAAGCUCAGUGAACAUACUGAAUUCACUUAUAAAAAGAAUUUUCUCAAUUUUAGUUGCUUUUCAAAAAAUUCUUAUUCCUUUUAUUUGUAAUUCUUUGACAUUGUUGCUGCUUCACAGUUUUGGUAAUUGGACAGUUUGGUCUUUAUUAUGAUAUUAACAUUUUUACCUGUCCUGAAACAAGGAAAUACAAUCAAAGAAACAGAAGAUUGGUGGACCUUGAACCACAUUAUGAUAUCAGAUGACCCAGAGUCAUGGUUACUAAGUUGCUUAAAUUUUUAGUAACAAAGAUGUAUUAGAAAGUGACAGGUCAAUUCAAUAAUGGUUUUUUUGGAUACAUUUAAUUAUAUAAUCCCCUUAAGUUGUGCUUAGUCAGCAGUAUUUAAUCUGUUGUCUAUUAUAUAUCUAACUGGUCUGUUAUGUUUAUUAUAUAUUUAUAUAUUGCUUAUUCAUAUCUUAUUGGAGUAACUCAUUUUUAAAACAAUAUAUUUCAUCUCCUAGGAGAAGAGGAUCGAGUAUGUGUUUUUAUUCUUUUUCAUUAGGACAUUGGGGUAUUUUCUUAUUGUGAAAUGUAUUGAAUAUUUCAUUUAUUUGGUUUGUGAGUCUGACCUUCACUCCCUAGCACUGAUUUUUAUUUGGCCCUCCUUUUACCUGAUUCAUAGGAGUUACGAGUAGCCGUUAAUAUGGAUACAUUUUUCCCAUUUCUAGUACACUGCCCCUUCCAAAAGUGUCUGGCUUACUCAAACUUUUCUGUAUUUGUUCCAUCUUGCUUUUACAGAUCAAUACAAAUAGGUAACUAUACCUUCUAAACAAACAUCAAGUUGGUGGAAAAAAGGCAUAUGAACAGUUCUUUCUCACCUACUAUCAACAAACAGUAAAUUAAACAUUCCUAACUGCAGCCUCCUUUUGUAAAAUUUAUAACCAUUUAUCUUUUGAGUGUGACAUGAUACUAGAUGUAUGAUAAUUACAUGUUUUGUGUAUCAGUAUGAACAUGAUUUUUAACAGACUUGUUCCAAUGAACUAUUAUAGAGAUGGUCCCCAACAAUGUCAACUAACAAUUUCUCAGCUUUAUGAUGGUACAAAAGUGAUAUGUUGCUAUAGUUUGGAUAUUUGUCCCUCCAAAUCUCAUGUUGAAGUUUGAUCUCAGUGUUGGAGGUGGGGCCUAAUGGAAGGUGUUUGGGUCAUGGUGGAAGAUCCCUCAUGAAUAAAUUAAUGCCCUCUCUGGAUUGAGGGGUGAGUGAGCUAUCGCUCUGUUAAUUUUUGUGAGAGCUGGUUGUUCAAAAGAACCUGGCACCUCCUCCCUCACCCUCUUGUUUUCUCUCUUGCCAUGUGAUGUCUGCAUACACUGGCUCUCCCUUCAUCAUCUGCCAUGAGUGGAAGCAGCCUGAGACCCUUAGCAGAAGCAGAUGCUGCACCAUGAUUCUUGUACAUUCUGCAGAACAGUGAGCCAAAUAAACCUCUUUAUUAAUCA